AGUCCUCGCUUCCCUGGGAGGGGGAAGAGUUUCACUCUGGCUCCUAGGCUGGAAUGCAGUGGCACCAUCUCAGCUCUCUGCAACCUCCACUUCCCAGGUUCAAGCGAUUCUCCUGCCUCACCCUCCUGAGUAGCUGGGACUACAGGCGAGCACCACCACAGCCGGCUAAUUUUUCUAUUUCUAGUAGAAAUGGGGUUUCACCAUGUUGGCAGGCUGGUCUCGAACUCUGACCUCAAGUGAUCUGCCUGCCUCAGCCUCUGAAAGUGCUGGAUUGCAGGCGUGAGCCACCGCACCAGGCCUAAACAGAUUUCUUUACAAUCUACCACCAUGAACAGCAAGCAUUAGCAUUGGCUCUUCCUUCUGCCCAGCUCCGUCCCACCCAGCAGCCCGCAGAGAAAGGAGGCAGCUGGCACCACACUGGGCUUUGGAGACACUGCGGGGACUGUGGACCCCACCCUGCUGCACGGAGCUCCUGCAAAAGCAAACCUGAGAACCUUGCAUACAGAUCCCUGCAAGAGGCAUCUGUCUCCAGUGGUCCAGCCUCUCCUUCCAAAUGAAAAGAAUCAAGUCACAGGAAUUCAUGGGUCUGUAAGGAAUCGCUCCCAUCUGUGCCCAGGAGAUUAACAAAGGCGGUGGCUGCAGCUCUGUGAGCAGUGGAGAAAAAUUAGGCACAACCUGAUAUCCUCCCACAGGAGCGGUCCUCCCAGCGCCCAGCCAUGGGGGAACUGUGCCGCAGGGACUCCGCACUCACGGCACUGGACGAGGAGACACUGUGGGAGAUGAUGGAGAGCCACCGCCACAGGAUCGUACGCUGCAUCUGCCCCAGCCGCCUCACCCCCUACCUGCGCCAGGCCAAGGUGCUGUGCCAGCUGGACGAGGAGGAGGUGCUGCACAGCCCCCGGCUCACCAACAGCGCCAUGCGGGCCGGGCACUUGCUGGAUUUGCUGAAGACUCGAGGGAAGAACGGGGCCAUCGCCUUCCUGGAGAGCCUGAAGUUCCACAACCCUGACGUCUACACCCUGGUCACCGGGCUGCAGCCUGAUGUUGACUUCAGUAACUUUAGCGGUCUCAUGGAGACAUCCAAGCUGACCGAGUGCCUGGCUGGGGCCAUCGGCAGCCUGCAGGAGGAGCUGAACCAGGAAAAGGGGCAGAAGGAGGUGCUGCUGCGGCGGUGCCAGCAGCUGCAGGAGCACCUGGGCCUGGCCGAGACCCGUGCCGAGGGCCUGCACCAGCUGGAGGCUGACCACAGCCGCAUGAAGCGUGAGGUUAGCGCACACUUCCAUGAGGUGCUGAGGCUGAAGGACGAGAUGCUCAGCCUCUCGCUGCACUAUAGCAAUGCGCUGCAGGAGAAGGAGCUGGCCGCCUCACGCUGCCGCAGCCUGCAGGAGGAGCUGUAUCUACUGAAGCAGGAGCUGCAGCGAGCCAACAUGGUUUCCUCCUGUGAGCUGGAAUUGCAAGAGCAGUCCCUGAGGACAGCCAGCGACCAGGAGUCCGGGGAUGAGGAGCUGAACCGCCUGAAGGAGGAGAAUGAGAAACUGCGCUCGCUGACUUUCAGCCUGGCGGAGAAGGACAUUCUGGAGCAGAGCCUGGACGAGGCGCGGGGGAGCCGACAGGAGCUGGUGGAGCGCAUCCACUCGCUGCGGGAGCGGGCCGUGGCUGCCGAGAGGCAGCGAGAGCAGUACUGGGAAGAGAAGGAACAGACCCUGCUGCAGUUCCAGAAGAGUAAGAUGGCCUGCCAACUCUACAGGGAGAAGGUGAAUGCGCUGCAGGCCCAGGUGUGCGAGCUGCAGAAGGAGCGAGACCAGGCGUACUCCGCGAGGGACAGUGCUCAGAGGGAGAUUUCCCAGAGCCUGGUGGAGAAGGACUCCCUCCGCAGGCAGGUGUUCGAGCUGACGGACCAGGUCUGCGAGCUGCGCACACAGCUUCGCCAGCUGCAGGCAGAGCCUCCGGGUGUGCUCAAGCAGGAAGCCAGGACCAGGGAGCCCUGUCCACGGGAGAAGCAGCGGCUGGUGCGGAUGCAUGCCAUCUGCCCCAGAGACGACAGCGACUGCAGCCUCGUCAGCUCCACAGAGUCUCAGCUCUUGUCGGACCUGAGUGCCACGUCCAGCCGCGAGCUGGUGGACAGCUUCCGCUCCAGCAGCCCCGCGCCCCCCAGCCAGCAGUCCCUGUACAAGCGGGUGGCCGAGGACUUCGGGGAAGAACCCUGGUCUUUCAGCAGCUGCCUGGAGAUCCCGGAGGGAGACCCGGGAGCCCUGCCGGGAGCUAAGGCAGGCGACCCACACCUGGAUUAUGAGCUCCUAGACACGGCAGACCUUCCGCAGCUGGAAAGCAGCCUGCAGCCAGUCUCCCCUGGAAGGCUUGAUGUCUCGGAGAGCGGCGUCCUCAUGCGGCGGAGGCCAGCCCGCAGGAUCCUGAGCCAGGUCACCAUGCUGGCGUUCCAGGGGGAUGCAUUGCUGGAGCAGAUCAGCGUCAUCGGCGGGAACCUCACGGGCAUCUUCAUCCACCGGGUCACCCCGGGCUCGGCGGCGGACCAGAUGGCCUUGCGCCCGGGCACCCAGAUUGUGAUGGUUGAUUACGAAGCCUCAGAGCCCUUGUUCAAGGCAGUCCUGGAGGACACGACCCUGGAGGAGGCCGUGGGGCUUCUCAGGAGGGUGGACGGCUUCUGCUGCCUGUCUGUGAAGGUCAACACGGACGGUUAUAAGAGGCUACUCCAGGACCUGGAGGCCAAAGUGGCGACCUCGGGGGACUCAUUCUACAUCCGGGUCAACCUGGCCAUGGAGGGCAGGGCCAAAGGGGAGCUGCAGGUGCAUUGCAACGAGGUCCUGCACGUCACCGACACCAUGUUCCAGGGCUGCGGCUGCUGGCAUGCCCACCGCGUGAACUCUUACACCAUGAAGGAUACUGCCGCGCACGGCACCAUCCCCAACUACUCCAGGGCUCAGCAGCAGCUCAUAGCCCUCAUCCAGGACAUGACUCAGCAGUGCACCGUGACCCGCAAGCCAUCUUCUGGGGGACCACAGAAGCUGGUCCGCAUCGUCAGUAUGGACAAAGCCAAGGCCAGCCCUCUGCGUUUGUCCUUUGACAGGGGCCAGUUGGACCCCAGCAGGAUGGAGGGCUCCAGCACGUGCUUCUGGGCCGAGAGCUGCCUCACCCUGGUGCCCUAUACCCUGGUGCGGCCCCAUCGACCCGCCCGGCCCCGGCCUGUGCUCCUCGUGCCCAGGGCGGUUGGGAAGAUCCUGAGCGAGAAACUGUGCCUCCUCCAAGGGUUUAAGAAGUGCCUGGCAGAGUACUUGAGCCAGGAGGAGUAUGAGGCCUGGAGCCAGAGAGGGGACAUCAUCCAGGAGGGAGAGGUGUCCGGGGGCCGCUGCUGGGUGACCCGCCAUGCUGUGGAGUCCCUCAUGGAAAAGAACACCCAUGCCCUCCUGGACGUCCAGCUGGACAGUGUCUGCACCCUGCACAGGAUGGACAUCUUCCCCAUCGUCAUCCACGUCUCUGUCAACGAGAAGAUGGCAAAGAAGCUCAAGAAGGGCCUACAGCGGUUGGGCACCUCAGAGGAGCAGCUCCUGGAGGCUGCGAGGCAGGAGGAGGGAGACCUGGACCGGGCGCCCUGUCUAUACAGCAGCCUGGCUCCUGACGGCUGGAGCGACCUGGACGGCCUGCUCAGCUGUGUCCGCCAGGCCAUCGCCGACGAGCAGAAGAAGGUGGUGUGGACGGAGCAGAGCCCCCGAUGAUGCACCGUGCCCCUUCCCGGGACUGUGGGGGCUUCUGUGUGCCUGUUAAUGCAGUCCUGUUCCUCAGCCCAGGCCCUCUUGGCACAGCUGUGGGCUCCUUGGCACAUGAGGCCGGCUCUCCCCACUGGCUGGGGUCUAACCUUGAACCCUCACCACGUGCAGGUCACACACAGUGAAGCCACUUGUAACUGCACACUUUUCUGUGGAAACAUCUUCACCCUUUACCAGGCUUGGCAUGGUCUGAACUGGAAACCCUGAGAAUGUUUCUGCAGUGGGACAGGAGGGACGUCUUCCCAUGCCUUCCCUAGAACCGGAGGCCCCGGACUUCUCUGGAAAACCGCCUGUCUGCAGGCCCGAUUCAAAUCUAUGGGGGCUGCACUUCCCUUUUACAUUUUGAUGUGUCAAAGGCUUUUGGAGUGACCAAAAGCACAGAGGCAGCGGGUGGGGCGCCUGGGUGGUCCCCAAGGUCGCUGCCACCCUUGCCCGGGGCAGAGGCAGAAGCCCACAUAUGCUGUGACGCUGGCCACCUUUUCUCAGCUUCUGAGGCUGCGAUGCCUCAGGAACUCCAGUUUACAGAGACCAGUGUGUUUACUUGUAAAUAAAGCCUCUGCGUGGUGGAGACGGUACUUUCAGUGGGUCUGUGCCCCGUGGCCCCUGUGCCUGUUCGGUGGGGGUGUCCCAGAGAAGCCUGGCACCAGUACCCCCGUACAAGGCCCAGCGGACUCUGCCUUCCCCUGACCUGGCUUUGCACCCCAGCCCUUCUUGGGCCAAACAUCUUUACUCCACCUUCAGGGCUCGGGGAGGACCCAGGUCCGCCAGCACCUGGCCUUGCCCCUGCCUCCUGGGGCUGUUGCAGACUGAAUGUCAUUUUGACAGCAGUGUCCAAGAAUCAGGAAGCUGUUCUAGAAUUCAGGUUGGUAUCAUCAUAAAUGAGUUCAGAAAAAGAACUUCUGUAUAUUUUACUAAAAUAAAAAGCUUUUACAAUA